UUACUUUUGUUAUGUAUUUUACCACAAUUUUUAAAAAGCAAACCAAAACCAACCAAGAGUGCUUCCCCCACACCUCAAAAUCAUCCUGCAGCAGCUCCCUGGCCCAGCUCUCUCUCACCCUGACCCUGGGCCCCUCUCCCACCACCCAGGGCUAGCCCUGUGGACCAACCAUCUCUGCCAGCCCCUCCCCGACCCUCCAGCCAGGGAGGUGGGGCGCUGGCCGGUGAAUGGGGCAGGCCAGGCCCAAAGGCUGGCCCAGGGCUCACCAGCUCUGGACUGGGCGUCCCGUCUGAGGUGGGGAUGACCAACAUGCCAGCUCUGGGUUUUAGCUGAGGAUGGGCACAUCAAGCACUGACAGCCAGCAAGCUGGGCACAGGCGAUGCUCAACCUCUAACACAUCGGCUGAGAACCUCACCUGCCUCUCCCUGCCUGGGAGCCCUGGCAAGACAGCUCCUCUCCCAGGCCCAGCACAGGCAGGCGCUGGACAGCCACUUCCUAAGGGGUGCGCGGCCGUCAAGGCAGAGGUGGGUAUCCCUGCACCUCACACCUCUCAGGAGGUCAGGAUCCACAUCCGUCGCCUGCUUUCCUGGGCUGCCCCUGGGGCUUGUGGGCUGAGAUCAACCCCUUGUGCCCUGCCCCAGGCCCUCCCUCAGGCGAGGCCCUGCCCAGGCAGGUGGUUCUUCCCUGGCUGUUCCCUUCCAACAGGUGGGGCCCAGACCAUCCUAUCUCUUUGGACCUGGAGACAUUUCCUUAACUGGGCUUUGCAGCAGAGGGAAGAGAACAGUGGCAGAGCCAGGCGCGUACCUCCUGUGCCCAGGACAGCACCUGUAAGCAAGGGGGAAGGGAGCCACCCACCCCAGAACUCAAAUGGAGAGAAAGUCAAGACAAUCACCCCUGACGUGGGGCUGCACCAAUCCCUGACGUCUGACCCCACUGUGGCUGUCCUCAGAGCCAAGAGGGCUCCAGAAGCCCACCCGCCUCGAAGCUGUUCAGGGAGCCUCACGGCCCGUGUUUGCCACAUGGGUGUGUGCCAGGGCCAAGGGGACACAGAAGAUGGCAGGAUGACACUAAUGGGGUGAGCAGGGCACACUGGUGCCUCCCAUACUGCCCUCCAGCACCAGGCAGGGUCACCACAGCCGGCAAGCACUGGGCCUGGGGAUGUGUGAAGAGAUAGGGUUAUUGAGAAGAGAAAACAGAACGCUGGUCAUCCGUGGCACUCAGGGCUAGGCAGUCCAGGGAGCAGAAAACAGGGGUCCCGGGCCCAGUCUCCCUCCUGGAGGUCAGAGCGGAGCCCCUGGCACUGUGCCCUGGCCCAGAACCAGGCUGUGGGCUCCACGCUGCACACCCCAACUCAGGAGCAGAAAGCAAACCCCU